GUGGUCUGCGCGCGCCCGGCCGUGCGUGCGGAUGCGGGGAGGCUGCGUGUGUGCGCAGGGAGAGAACGCCGGCCACCUUCCCGCUUCCGAGCUGGGUGCGCGCCGAGCACAGGAGGUGAGUGAGAAGGGCGGCCCUGCAGGGUCUCCGAGGCGGUUGAGUCCUGCCACUGGGUGGAGGGUAUAGCCACCGGACCCGCCUUUCCCGGAACGCGCCGUCCUCGGAAACGCCUAGACCCCGGCAGCUAGGCCGGGAGGCACCGCCCACUCCUCUAGAGCGGAGCGUGGCCCAGGUUGAGCCGCCGCACCGUGGGUCUCGGGUCUCGGUGACGAGCAGCUGCCCGCCUCCGGUGAGCGCGGGAGAAGGGGCCCAGUGGGGCAGUGGGCGACGCGGAGGGCCCAGGCCCAGGCCGCGGCCGCGCCGCAUCCGCUGGUUGUCCACCUUGCCUUGCCCCAGGGUGCAAUACCUGCCUUGCGUCGCCCGUGCCGCUCCAGCCACCGUCAAAUCCGGGUAGCGACCCGGGGCGUUUGCAGCGGUGCCGAGGAAGAGGACGGGAACGGUGUUACGAUUGCCUGCGUUUAGGAGGUGGCUGCGUUGUGGGAAAAGCUAUCAAGGAAGAAAUUGCCAAACCAUGUCUUUUUUUCUGUUUUCAGAGACUAAAAUGUUCGUUCAAAUGAAUGGCCAUUGGAUAACUCCAGACCUGAAAAUAAACACUGUUGUCAAAACAGCAUCCAGGCCGGGCGCGGUGGCUCACGCCAGUAAUUCCAGCACUUUGGGAGGCCGAGGCGGGCAGAUCACCUCAGUAGUUCACAACAGAUCUGAGUGUUUUAAUUAAGCAUGGAAUACAGAAAACAACAAAAAACUUAAGCUUUAAUUUCAUCUGGAAUUCCACAGAGACAAGGCCACUUUAUGUUUCCCAGGCUGGACUGGAACCCCUGGGCUCAAAUGAUCCUCCUACCUAAGCCUGCAGAGUAGCGAGGACUUCAGUUUUCUUAGCUCCCUGGACCCGGUUGACCUGUUGGCUCUUCCCGCUGGCUGCUCUAUCACGUGGUGCUCUCCGACUACUCACCCCGAGUGUAAAGAACCUUCGGCUCGCGUGCUUCUGAGCUGCUGUGGAUGGCCUCGGCUCUCUGGACUGUCCUUCCGAGUAGGAUGUCACUGAGAUCCCUCAAAUGGAGCCUCCUGCUGCUGUCACUCCUGAGUUUCUUUGUGAUGUGGUACCUCAGCCUUCCCCACUACAAUGUGAUAGAACGCGUGAACUGGAUGUACUUCUAUGAGUAUGAGCCGAUUUACAGACAAGACUUUCACUUCACACUUCGAGAGCAUUCAAACUGCUCUCAUCAAAAUCCAUUUCUGGUCAUUCUGGUGACCUCCCACCCUUCAGAUGUGAAAGCCAGGCAGGCCAUUAGAGUUACUUGGGGUGAAAAAAAGUCUUGGUGGGGAUAUGAGGUUCUUACAUUUUUCUUAUUAGGCCAAGAGGCUGAAAAGGAAGACAAAAUGUUGGCAUUGUCCUUAGAGGAUGAACACCUUCUUUAUGGUGACAUAAUCCGACAAGAUUUUUUAGACACAUAUAAUAACCUGACCUUGAAAACCAUUAUGGCAUUCAGGUGGGUAACUGAGUUUUGCCCCAAUGCCAAGUACGUAAUGAAGACAGACACUGAUGUUUUCAUCAAUACUGGCAAUUUAGUGAAGUAUCUUUUAAACCUAAACCACUCAGAGAAGUUUUUCACAGGUUAUCCUCUAAUUGAUAAUUAUUCCUAUAGAGGAUUUUACCAAAAAACCCAUAUUUCUUACCAGGAGUAUCCUUUCAAGGUGUUCCCUCCAUACUGCAGUGGGUUGGGUUAUAUAAUGUCCAGAGAUUUGGUGCCAAGGAUCUAUGAAAUGAUGGGUCACGUAAAACCCAUCAAGUUUGAAGAUGUUUAUGUCGGGAUCUGUUUGAAUUUAUUAAAAGUGAACAUUCAUAUUCCAGAAGACACAAAUCUUUUCUUUCUAUAUAGAAUCCAUUUGGAUGUCUGUCAACUGAGACGUGUGAUUGCAGCCCAUGGCUUUUCUUCCAAGGAGAUCAUCACUUUUUGGCAGGUCAUGCUAAGGAACACCACAUGCCAUUAUUAACUUCACAUUCUACAAAAAGCCUAGAAGGACAGGAUACUUUGUGGAAAGUGUUAAAUAAAGUAGGUACUGUGGAAAAUUCAUGGGGAGGUCAGUGUGCUGGCUUACACUGAACUGAAACUCAUGAAAAACCCAGACUGGAGACUGGAGGGUUACACUUGUGAUUUAUUAGUCAGGCCCUUCAAAGAUGAUAUGUGGAGGAAUUAAAUAUAAAGGAAUUGGAGGUUUUUGCUAAAGAAAUUAAUAGGACCAAACAAUUUGGACAUGUCAUUCUGUAGACUAGAAUUUCUUAAAAGGGUGUUACUGAGUUAUAAGCUCACUAGGCUGUAAAAACAAAACAAUGUAGAGUUUUAUUUAUUGAACAAUGUAGUCACUUGAAGGUUUUGUGUAUAUCUUAUGUGGAUUACCAAUUUAAAAAUAUAUGUAGUUCUGUGUCAAAAAACUUCUUCACUGAAGUUAUACUGAACAAAAUUUUACCUGUUUUUGGUCAUUUAUAAAGUACUUCAAGAUGUUGCAGUAUUUCACAGUUAUUAUUAUUUAAAAUUACUUCAACUUUGUGUUUUUAAAUGUUUUGACGAUUUCAAUACAAGAUAAAAAGGAUAGUGAAUCAUUCUUUACAUGCAAACAUUUUCCAGUUACUUAACUGAUCAGUUUAUUAUUGAUACAUCACUCCAUUAAUGUAAAGUCAUAGGUCAUUAUUGCAUAUCAGUAAUCUCUUGGACUUUGUUAAAUAUUUUACUGUGGUAAUAUAGAGAAGAAUUAAAGCAAGAAAAUCUGAAGUAUUGUCUUGUUUUUAAAAAAUACAGUUCCUAGUGUUUUUAGAAGUCACUUAAUUUGUCUCAUUUUUCCACCUGGAAAUUAGGAAUAAUGUAGAAUGCAAGGCAGUAAUUUCCUUUUGGAAAGGACUCUGAAGGCAGAAAAGAAGGGAGAGAACCUCAUGGGCAGAAUAUUAUAAAAAGAGUGUCAUAUUCCAGCAUUUGAAUUGGAAAGAGAAGAGUGAAGAUCCAAGUUGCAUUAUUAAUCUGCCCUGUGUUUUUUCCUUUUAACAAUCAGUUUGAGCUGCUGCUGUUAUGAGUUUCUCAUCAAGAUGAAAGCCCUAAUAUGUAAAGUCAAAUCCGAUUUAAAUUUUGUGCUUUUAUAGAAAGAAAUUUCUUCAUAGACGUGGUGAUAUAUCAUUUGUUGGACCUGCUAAUAGUAGGUCAAAGGGGAGCACUCCUUGCCCCCUGUUCCUGGGUUUAUGCAGUUUUCUUUUUAGAGUUUAUAUAGGGCAAGUGGUUCUUUUUCUCUGAAUUACAGGAUGGAAAAAGGUCAUAUCCUUUGUCAGGAAAUAUAAACUUGAAAGUAUGUAGUCAGCUCUUGUAAUACUCAUAUUUAUGAUUGUCCUAUAUGAAAAACAACUUCAGUUAAAACUAUAAUGUGUGAUUCUGUAUAACAAGGUGAUGUCUGUUUCCCAGGGCUCAGACCUAAUCCAGUUAUAAUAAAAUCAAUUAAAUGAAAUAUUCUAUAGAAUCGAUCUAUGCCCUUGUUAAUCUCCAUCCAUAUAGGAGUCACGUUCUUUAAGACAGAUGGUGGUAGUUAUUUUUGUGGCAUGGUUAGAUUUGACUGGUUUUGCAGAAGAUUACAGUUAUGUACUGCAUAAUGACAUAUACAAUAGUGGUCCCAUAAAAUUAUAAUGGAGCAGAAAAUCUAUUGCCUCAUGAUGUUUUAGCCGUUUUAAUGUCAUAGCCUAGUGCAUUACUCACGUGUCUGUGGAGAUGCUGGUGUAAACAAACCUACUACACUGCCAGUUGUAUAAAAGUACAGCACAUUCAGUUAUGUACAGUAUGUAAUACUGAUAAUGACAAUAAAUGACACCGGUUUGUGUAUUUACUUUUUAUAA